UAACCUGGUCUUACCAUGGCCCUGUCCCUCCCCUGGCUCUGUCCUGGUCUUAUGCUGACCCUGACCCAGACCUUGGCCCUGCCACAGCCUUGUCCUAGACCUGGCCAUGGCCCUGCGUCUGCCCUGGACCGGCACUGGCACUGGCAUGGACCCUGGCCCUGGCCCUUCACUACUUAAGGCCAUACCCUGGCCCAGCCCUGGCCCUAAUUUGGCCUGGCUCUACCCUGGCAUGCUAUUCUGGCCCUAGCCCUGACCCUGUCCCUGUCCCUGUCCUGGUCCUAGCCCCGUUGCUGGUCCUGCCAUGGCCCUUGUCCUGACAUUGCCCUUUCCUGGUUCUGGCCCUGGCCCUGUCCCAGCCCUGCUCUGGCCCUGGUCUGAACCCUGGCCCUGCAAUAGACCUGCCUUGGUCCUGCCCAGACCCUGGCUCUGGCCCUACCUCUGCCCUGGCCAUACCCUUGCCCUGGCCUGGACCCCGGUCCUGGUCCUUGUCCUGCCCCAGCCGUGGCCCUGGCCCUGCCCUGCCUGUGCCCUGUUCUAUCCUGGGCUGGCCCUGCCAUGGCCUGGUCUUGCCAUUGCCCUGCCCUAGCUUGCCCUGCUUGUGCCCUAGAUCUGCCCCGCUUGUGCCCUAGAUCUGCCCCGGCCUUUGCCCCAUCUUGGUUCUAGCCUUGACUCAGCCCUGGACCUUCCCUGACCUUGCCUCAGCCCUGGCACUACCCUGGCAUUGCCUUGGCAUUUGCCCUACUCUCUCUAUGGCCUGGCUGUGGUCCUGCCCUGCUCUGCUCUUGUUCUGUCCUGGCACAGCCCUGGCCCUGGCCCUGGCCCUGCCGUAUCACUGGCUCUGGUCCUGCCCUUAUGCAGACCUGACCCUGCCACUGCCUUGGCUUUGGCCUGGACCUUGGCCAUACAGUGACCCUGCCAUGACAUUUUCCUGGUCCUGGCCUGGAACCUGGCCCUGCCAAGGACUCGCCCUGGCUCUGUCAUGGCCCUGGCCCGUUCCUGGAUUUGGAUGUGUCCUGUCCCUUAUUUGCCCCGGCCCUUCCCUGGCUCUGCCAUACCCCUUCUCUGGGGUAGGGCCAGGGUCAGGACCAGACCAGGGCAGGGUCAGGACCAGGGUAGGGCCAUGUUAAGGCCUGAAGAUGGGAAGGGCCAGGGCAGCGGCUGGACCAGGGAAGGGUCAGGGCCAGGGAUGUAGUAGGACUAGGGGCAGAGCCGGCACUAGGGCUGAGCCAGGGCAGAGCAGGAGAGAUUACUUUAGGCUAUUACUAAAAUUUUUAUUUUAGAUUUUUAAGAUAACUAUAGUAGUAGUAAUGUCUAUACUAUGUUGUUUGUAAUAGUAAUAAUACUUGCAGUAAUCACUAAAUUUUAACUAAUACUAUCUUUGCUUCCAGUAGUGUUCUAUGAGUAUAAUUUUAUCAACAUGUAAAUAUGUGAGGCAUUGAUUCUCAUAAUAAUUCUAUAUGCUAGGUACUUAAAGCAUCCCCAUUUUCCAAAUGUAGGAAACAGGCAAAAAGAAGGUAAAUACUUGGCCAGAUUACUCCUGUAAUCCCAGCACUUUGGGAGGCCAAGGCAGGCAGAUGGCUUGAGCUCAGGAGUUUGGAACCAGCCUGGGCAACAUUGUGAAACCCCAUCUCUACUAAAAAUGCACAAAAAGAACUAAUUUAAGUUUCUUGUAGGAUUCUGGUUAUAAAACACUGGUCAAACACACAGGGCAUGGAUAGGGCAGGGCCAGGGACAAGGUCAGGCCAGGAAGGGGCCAGGGCCAAGGCAGGGCCAGAGCUGGACUUGGAGGUGUCCUGGUCUGAUUUGCCCUGCCCCAACGUUGGCCCAGCCCUGCUCUGGCACGUCCUGUCAUGCCCUGUCCCUGGCCUGAGCAUUGGCCCUGGCCCUGUCCUGCUUCUGGCCCUGCCCCGGAGUUGACCAGGCACUGCCAUGGCCCAGUCCUGCAUUGCCCUGCCCUCCUCUGCCCUGGUGCUACCAUGGCGCUGCUUGGGCCCUAGCUCUGCCUCGACUCUGGACCUGCCCUGACUCUGCUCAGCCCUGGAUCUACCCUGACUCUGCCUUGGUGUUGCCCUCCCAUCUCUAUGGCCUGGCUCUGGCCAUGCCUUGCACAGACCAUGCUCUGCCCUGCGUGCCCCAGCCUGGGCCCAGCCCUCAUCCUACCAUAUUCCUGACCCCAGCCAUACCCUUGUUCUCGCCAUGACCCUGCCGUGGCCCUCUCCUGGCCCUUCCUUGAUCCUGCCCUGCCCUUCCAUGCCCUGGCCUUGCCCUCACCCUGCAUUGGCCCUGCACUGGUCCUGCCCUGCCCUGGCACUGCCUUGGCCCUGGCCCUGCCUUCUUCCUGGCCUUGCCUUUGCCCUGCCCUGGCCUGACCCCAGGCCUACUGAGUCCAUGAAAUGGCCCUGGACCUGCCUUGCCAUCCUCUGUCCUGGCCCUAUAUUGUCCCCACCAUGCUCUGGUCCAGCGCUUGCCCUAGCCCUGUUGCUAGUCCUGCCACUGCUAUGGCCCUGCUCUGUUUUUGGCCGUGCCCUGUGCUACCCUAGCCCUGCCCUGCCUUGGCCUUGGCCCUACCAUGGCCUUCUCCUACCCUGGCCUGGCCCUACCCUGGCCUUUUCUACCCUGGCCUUGCCCUUCCCUGGUGUUGCCCUGCCCUGGCCUUGCCCUGCCCUGGCCUUGGCUUUGCCUUAUCCUGGUCCUGGUUCUGCCCUGACCCUGGCCUUGCUCUGGAUCCUCUCUGGUUCUGCUUUCUCCCUGGCCCUGCCCUUGCUCUGGCCCUGUCCCUGGACCAGCCUUGACCCUGACCCUGACAAUCCCCAGGUCUGACACUGGCCAUGCUUGGCCCUGGCCCCUCCUUUUGGCCCUGCCUUAGCCCUGUGCUAUCUUAGUCCUGCCCUGGCCCUGAACUCGCCCUGGUCCUACCCUCACCCUACACUGGCCCUGCCCUAUCCUGGCCUUGCCCUGCCCUGGCCCUGCCUUUGGCCUGCUCUGGCUCUGGUUCUGCCCUGGACUUGCCCUUGCCCUGGACCCUCCCUGGCCAUGUUUUUCCCAUGGUCCUUCUCUGGCCUUGCCCUUGCCCUGUCCCCUUUCUGGUCCUGCCAUGUUUCUGGCCCUGCCCUGUCCAGGUCCUGGACCUGACUCUGGCCCUGGACCUCCCUGUCCCUGCCCUGCCAUACCCUGGCCCGUUCCUUGCUCUACACUGACCCUGCCCUGCCUUGGCCCUGUGCCACCCUAGCCCUGCCCUGGCCUUCUGCUGACCCUGAUCCUGCCAUGGCCCUGGCCCUGCCAUGUCCCUGCCCUGGCCCUGGUUCUUCCCUGCUUCUGGACCUGGCCUUGGUCCUCUCAUGUCCCUGGCUGUGACCCUGCCCCUGGUUUUUCUCUGGCCAUGACCCUGCCCCAGUUCUGUCCUAUCCCUGGCCCUGUCUCAGUUCUGUCCUAGCCCUGGCCUUUCACAGUACUUUAUGCUUAGUAAGGGCUCCAUGGUGUCUGUGAGUUGAAUGUUGUGUUCAUAGUAUCUGCCAAAACAGAAAGAAAAAAGUAAAAUAUUUUGAUAAGAAGUUAAAGCUUUGUAUAUAAUAUGCCUUGAAUUGUAAGUGCCUGUUAUUAGUUGUAUUACAUAUGGGUCAUGGCUUUGUACACGUAACUCCAAACCAUUGAUACUGUUAAAAGGAUAUAUGAAUAUAUGAAAGAAUGUAUAAACGUAAGAAUGUAUCAGUAUCUAAUGACCUUUCCAAAUUAAUUUUUAUUUUUAGCUCUAUUAGAUUUUUCUCAGUGUAACAAAUGUUUAUUCUUAUGUAAUUAAGGGUGUGUUUCCUGUACAGAAUAUUCAUAAUACCUAAUUGAAAAUUAUAUGAUACAAAAAUAUAAUACUAUUUUUAGGCCAAGCAUGGUGGCUCAUACCUGUAAUCCCAACA